CCUUUUGUGACGCCGGCUGUGAGCGCCUGAGAGUCUUUUUGCCUUUCAGAGUUAAGGCCUCACUGGCCUGGGUGAGUUCCGAGGAGAUGAACUGGUUUUGGGGUGAAGGACGGGUUUGGCCCGGACGUUAGAGAGGCCUGGCCCGCUCUGCUCGUGUCUGCUGGGCCCGCUAGCGUCCGCUCGGACCGUCGCUCCUCGGGAGGAGUCGGGUUUAUAGUUACGGUGUCCGCAGGGUGUUUUCAUCUGUGCGCCCCUCUCCAAAGGCCUCCAAAGCAGCGUUUGUGAAUUUUUUUCCGGCAGGAAAAUAAUUGCUGCCUUUUGCAUCCGCGUUGGCUCCGUCCCCAGGAUCUUCCCGGUUCAGGGACCUGGCGAUUUCUGAGUGUUCCGGAAUCCCAAUAACCCUGUUUAAAGAGGAAUGGAGAUUGCCACUGUCCAUUUAGAUUAAUGAGGUGUCCUGAAGUGAUGGUGACAUCAAUGAAAGGAGGGUUCUGACACGUUCUCACCUCGCGGGAUGGCAGCUGCUGAUUUGUCCCAUGGAUUCAGUGACCUUUGACGAUGUGGCUGUGGACUUCACCCAGGAGGAGUGGACUUUACUGGACUCAACUCAGAGAAGCCUCUACAGUGACGUGAUGCUGGAGAACUACAAGAACCUGGCCACAGUAGGAGGUCAGAUCAUCAAACCCAGUCUAAUCUCUUGGUUGGAACAAGAAGAGUCAAGGACAGUUCAGGGAGGAGUUCUCCAAGGAUGGGAAAUGCGACUUGAAACCCAGUGGUCUAUACUUCAGCAGGACUUUUUGAGGGGUCAGACAUCCAUUGGGAUACAAUUGGAAGGAAAACACAAUGGAAGGGAACUCUGUGACUGUGAGCAAUGUGGAGAAGUCUUCAGUGAACACUCAUGCCUUAAGACGCACGUGAGAACUCAAAGUACAGGGAACACUCAUGACUGUAAUCAGUAUGGAAAAGAUUUCCUUACCCUGUGUGAGAAAACCUCUACUGGUGAGAAACUUUCUGAGUUUAAUCAGAGUGAAAAAAUCUUCAGCCUGACACCAAAUAUUGUAUACCAGAGAACUAGCACACAAGAAAAGUCAUUUGAAUGUAGUCACUGUGGAAAAUCCUUCAUUAAUGAGUCAUACCUUCAGGCACAUAUGAGAACUCACAAUGGAGAAAAACUCUACGAAUGGAGGAAUUAUGGGCCAGGUUUUAUUGACUCUACAAGCCUUUCUGUGCUUAUAGAAACCCUCAAUGCAAAAAAGCCCUACAAAUGUAAGGAAUGUGGAAAAGGCUAUAGAUACCCAGCCUACCUCAGUAUUCACAUGCGAACCCACACUGGGGAGAAACCAUAUGAAUGUAAGGAAUGUGGGAAAGCCUUCAAUUAUUCCAACUCAUUUCAGAUACAUGGAAGAACUCACACUGGAGAGAAACCCUAUGUAUGUAAGGAAUGUGGGAAAGCCUUCACUCAGUACUCGGGCCUUAGUAUGCAUGUACGAUCUCACAGUGGAGACAAGCCCUAUGAAUGUAAGGAAUGUGGGAAAUCCUUCCUUACAUCCUCACGCCUUAUUCAACAUAUAAGAACUCACACUGGAGAGAAGCCUUUUGUAUGUGUUGAAUGUGGGAAAGCCUUUGCAGUUUCCUCAAAUCUUAGUGGACAUUUGAGAACUCACACUGAAGAGAAGGCCUGUGAGUGUAAGAUAUGUGGGAAAGUAUUUGGGUAUCCCUCAUGUCUUAAUAAUCACAUGCGAACGCACAGUGCCCAGAAACCAUACACCUGUAAGGAAUGUGGGAAGGCUUUUAACUAUUCCACCCACCUUAAAAUUCACAUGCGAAUCCACACUGGAGAAAAACCCUAUGAGUGUAAACAAUGUGGAAAGGCCUUCAGUCAUUCCAGUUCAUUUCAAAUACAUGAAAGGACUCACACUGGAGAGAAACCCUAUGAAUGCAAGGAGUGUGGGAAAGCCUUCACGUGUUCCAGUUCCUUUAGAAUUCAUGAAAAAACUCACACAGAAGAGAAACCCUAUAAAUGUCAGCAAUGCGGGAAAGCUUACAGUCAUCCCCGUUCACUUCGAAGACAUGAACAAAUUCACUAGUGAGAAACUGUCCAUGUAAUAAAUGUGGGAAAGCUCUCAUUUGUUCCAGUUCACUUUAAAGACAUGAAUGAACUCACUCUGGAGAGAAGAAGCUGCAUGAAAAUUACUUAAUUCCUGUAAUCCCAGCAUUUUGAGAGGCUGAGGUGGGUGGAUCACUUGAGGUCAGGAGUUUGAGACCACCCUGGCCAACAUGGUGAAACCUUGUCUCUACUGAAAAUACAAAAAAUUUAGCCAGGUGUGGUGGGCACCUGUAAUCCCAGCUACUUGGGAGGCUGAGGCAAGUGAAUCACUUGAACCCAGGAAGCAGAGGUUGCAGUGAGCAGAGAUCAUGCCACUGCACUCCAGCCUGGGCGAUGGAGUGAGACUCCAUCUCAAAAAAAAAAAAAAAAGAAAAUUAUUUGAUUAAAUUGAGUCUGUUAGAGUACAUCCCUAAUCCAAUAUGAUUGGUGUCCCUAUAAGAAGAGAAAGACACAACUGAGACAACAAAUAGAAGAUGAUGUGAAGUCAUCAGAUGAUGGCCAUCUGCAAGCCAAAGACAGAGCACUGGGACAGAUCCUUCUAUCAAAGCCACCAACCCUGCUGGCACCUUCAUCUUGGGCUUCCAGAACUUUGAACAAAUAAAAUUCUCUUGUUUGAGCCACCCAGUCUGUGGUAUUUUGUUGUGGUGGCUCUAGCAAGUGAAUACAGUAAGCAAUAAGCAAAAACGUUUAUAGAUUGUCCAAAAGCCUUAAUAUUCACAUGCAAAGCCACACUGGAGAGAAACUAUAUGAAUGUAAGACGUGGGAGAGCCUUCAUUGAGUCUUCAGUCCUUUCUACAUACAGGAGAAAUCACAUAGGAGAGAAAUUGUAUGAAUGUAAGGAGCAUGAAAAAGCCUGUGAAUGUUCACUAUAUUUUAAUAUUCACAUGCAAGUUGUCUGGUCGUAGACCAUGUGAAAAUAGAGGAGAAAAAAGGAAAGAAAGUUUCUUUUACUGUGAACGCAAGGAAUGUGACCCCAUACACCAUACUGGAACUUGGAGUGGACUGAAAUCCCAUUAGGAUUGUGGAAAAGCUUACAUUAAUGUUUUCUACCUUCUAGAAGGUGUAAGAAGUCGAACUGGAGAGAAGCCUUUUACCUGUAAUGCAUGUAGGAAGCCUUACAUUAAUUCCACAGAAUUUUUUUUACACAUGUAAAAUUACCUCAGAACCCUGGGAAGGUAAGGAAUAUGGUAUAACCUUUAAAUAUUUCACAUGCCAUAAUAAGUACAUGAAUUCUGAUAAUACUGUACCGUUUCUUGAGUAGUGUUAGUACCUUAUACUAUCAAAAUAAUCCUAAAUCCUCCCUCUCAGACCUUCCAUCAUUACUAUAUUUCACUUUUAUGCCUAUAAACACACACAAAUUAGCAUAUGUAAUCUAAUACAUUGUAGCUAUUUUUCAGAAGUUAUCAGAUCAAUUAAGUAUUAGAAAAAUAAACAUUUUUAUUUUACCUUCACUUCUUCCUUCUAUGCUCAAAGUUGGAUGUAAUUCUUAUACUUGAUCCUCAAUACUUAAAGCAUUUCCCCCCCUCUGGCUUCUAUGAAAAUUUUUUGUUAUCUUUGAUAUUCUGUUAUUUUUAAAUGAUAUGCCUAGGUAUAGGUUUUUGGUGCUCGUCCUUCUUGGUGUUUGCUUAGCCUCCUGGAUUUGCGUUUUGGUGUCUGAGUUAAUUUUGAGAAAUUCUGUCAUUGUUUCCCUUUUUUUUUCUUUCCAUCUGGUAUUUCCUUUAUAUGUAGGAUACAUCUUUUGUAGUUAUCCCACAGUUCUUAUAUCUUGUUUUUUUAUUCUUCUCUUUGCUUUUCAGGUGUGGAUGUUUCUGCUGAUAUAUUCUCAAGCUCUUUAGUUGGCUGUUUCUUGGCCAAUAAUAAGCCUACCAAAGACAUUCUUCAUUUCUGUUACACUGUCUUCAAUUUCUAGCAUUUCUUUGUGGUUCUUAGAAUUUCCAUCUCUGUGUUUACACUGCCUGUCUGUUCUUGGAUGCUGUCUGCUUUAUCCAGUAGAACCCAUGGCAUAUCAAUCAUAAUUGUUUUAAAUUCCCAGUCUGAUAAUUUCAGCAAUCCUGCUAUAUCUGGUUCUGGUUCUUACUCUUUCUCUUUAAACUAACUUUUGCCUUUUAGUAUGCUUGUAAUUUUUCCUUAGCUGGACAUGGCAUACUGGAUAAGAGGAAAUGCUGUAAGCAGGCCUCUAGUAAUCAUGAUAAGCUGUGGGGAGAGGGGCAGCAUUCUAUUGUCCAGGGAUUAGAUGUCAGUCUUGCAGUGAGUCUGUGCUUCUGCACUGUGAACUUCAGUUUUUCCCACCCUUUAGUUGGGUCAGGAUGUAUAGAGUUGGCUGGAGUUGGAUAUUUCCCUUCCUCCAGGUCACUGAAGCUCUGACUAAAACUCCAGGUGUGGUGGCUUAUGCCUGUAAUACCAGCACUUUGGGAGGCCAAGGCAGGUGGAUCACCUGAGGUUGGGAGUUCAUGACCAGCCUGAAUUGCUUGAAUCCAGGAGGUGGAGGUCACAGUGAGCCGAGAUUGUGAUACUGCACUCCAGCCUGGGAAACAGUGAGACACUGUCUCAAAAAAAUAAAUAAAUAAAUAAAAGGCUAGGCGCAGUGGCUCAACCCUGUAAUCCCAGCACUUUGGGAGGCAGAGGUGGGUGGAUCAUGAGGUCAGGAGAUCGAGACCAUCCUGGCCAACAUGGUGAAACCCCGUCUCUACUAAAAAUACAAAAAAAUUAGCUGGGUGUGGUGGCGGGCACCUGUAGUCCCAGCUACUUGGGAGGCUGAGGCAGGAGAAUGGUGUGAACCCAGGAGGUGGAGCUUGCAGUGAGCCGAGAUCACGCCACUGCACUCCAGCCUGGGUGACAGAGUGAGACUCUGUCUCAAAACAACAACAACAACAACAACAACAAAAACCCAUCAUCAAUGCUCAGCCUUUCUUAAACAUGAACUCAUGGUGGACAGAGCCCUAUGAAUGUAAGGAAUAUAGAGAAGCCAUCACUAGUUACUCAAACCUUAUUGAAUGUGUGAAAAUUUACUCUGGAGAGAUGCCCUUUCAGCAUAAGAAAUGUUGAAAAGGAUUUAUAUAAUCCUUCCUUUUUAUUUUUAUUUUUAUUUUUAUUUUUAUUUUUAUUUUUUUUGAGACGGAGUCUCGCUCUGUCGCCCAGGCUGGAGUGCAGUGGUGCGAUCUCGGCUCACUGCAAGCUCCGCCUCCCGGGUUCACGCCAUUCUCCUGCCUCAGCCUCCCGAGUAGCUGGGACUACAGGCGCCCGCUACCACGCCCGGCUAAUUUUUUGUAUUUUUAGUAGAGACGGGGUUUCACUGUGUUAGCCAGGAUGGUCUCGAUCUCCUGACCUCGUGAUCCGCCCGCCUCGGCCUCCCAAAGUGCUGGGAUUACAGGCGUGAGCCACCGCGCCCAGCCAAUCCUUCCUUUUUAAUAUCCACAUACAAACUCACUGAAGAAAAACCCUGAAAAUGUAAAGCAAUGUUGAAAAACCUAGUUAUUUAAAUUCAUUUCAAGUAUAUGAACUCACAUGGUAAAGAAACCCUGUGAAUAUAAGUAGUAUGAUAAAUUCUUGAAUUUUUUUUUUUUUUUUUUUUUUUUUUUGAGGCAGAGUUUUGCUCUUGUUGCCCAGGCUGGAGUGCAAUGGCUCAAUCUUGGCUCACUACAACCUCUAUCACCCAGGUUCAAGUGAUUAUUCUGCCUCAGCCUCCCAAGUAGCUGGGAUUACAGGCAUGUACCACCAUGCCCAGCUAAUUUUGUAUUUUUAGUGAAGGCAGGGAUUCUCCAUGUUGAUCAGGCUGGUCUCGAACUCCUGACCUCCAGUGAUCUGCCUGGUUUGACCUCCCAAAGUGCUGAGAUUACAGGCAUGAGCCAUCACGCCCAGCCAGUUCUUCAAUUCUUACAGUCCCUUUCCAUGUCAUUAAAGAACUCACACUGGAGAGAAAUCUUAUCAAUGUUAGAAUUGUGGUAAAGCUCUCUGUUGUUCCCAUUUACAUGAAAGAUGUGAACAGUCACAUUGUAGAAAAAUGCUGUGAGAGUUGGGAAUCUGGAACCACUUCUUUAUUAUCUCAGGUCAUAAUGAACUUGUAAGAAUUCACAGUGGCAGGAAACCCUAUGUAAAUGGAAAAUAUGGGAAAGGCUUCAUUUAAUCCAUAGGACUGAUACCACAAAACUCCCACUAGGAGAAAACCUAUGUUUAUACGGAAUGUGGGAAAAUCUUCACUUAUUUCUCAAGCCUUAAAGUGUAUGUCAGGAUUCCCAGUGGAGAGAAGCCAUAUUGAUGUAAGGAAUGUGGGAAAGCCCUUGCCUGCCACUUAGUCCUUGAUAAACAUUUUAGAACACAAACUGGAGAGAAACUAUGAAUUCAAGGAUUGUGGGAAAACCCUUUUAUGUUCCACAAGCUUUAAUAUUCAUAUGCAAUGUAUGCUGGAGAAUAACUUGAUGACUAUAAUAAGUGGAAUGGCCUAGGUCAGGGAUCCCCAAACCCCUGGGCCAUGGACUGGUACUGGUCUGUGGCCUGCUAGGAUCCAGGGUGCACAGCAGGAGGUGAAUGUAGGAUGAGCAAACAUUACUGCCUGAGCUCAACUUUCUGUCAGAUCAGCAGUGGCAUUAGAUUCUCAUAGGAGCAUGAACUUUAUUGUGAACUGCACAUGCAAGGGAUCUAGGUUGCACACUCCUUAUGAGAAUCUAAUGCCUGAUGAUCUGAACUGGAACAGUUUAAUCCCCAACUCCAGUCCGUGGGAAAAAUGUCUUCCACGAAACUGGUCCCUGGUGCCAAAAAGUUAGGGGACCACUGAUUUAGAUUAUGUCACAUGUCCCAUCCACUCAUUAACAUUAAGGCUUUCAUCCCUGGGACCUCAAGAUAAUGGUGGUAUUUAGAGAUGUGGUUUUUUAAAGAGGUGAUUUUAAAAUGAGGCAGUUAGAAUGGGGCCCUCAUUCAAUAUGACUGGUUUCCUUAUAAGAAGUGAAAGAGAUACCAGGGUAGCAGGCACAGAAUUUUAUGUGAAGUGACCGGAAAUGGUUACCUUCAAGGCAAAGAGAGAUUCCUGGAGGAGAUCCUUCUUUUAAGGCUCAUUAUAGAGGAAAUCAUCCUUAUCUACACUUUGAUCCUGGACUUCCAGCCUCAAAAAUUAUGAGCAAAUAAAUUUCUGUUGUUUAAGCCA